AGAGAUGAAACAGAAGGAAAGGCAGAGGAGGAGGGAGAGAGAGAGAAGAGAAGAAAAAGAAAAAAGAACAUCAAUAAAAAGAAGUCAGAUUUGUUCGAAAUCUUGAGGUUCUCUCUGUGUGUCCUACAGGAGUCUUCAGGCCAGCUCCCUGUCGGAUGGCUUUUAUGAAAAAAUAUCUCCUCCCCAUUCUGGGGCUCUUCAUGGCCUACUACUACUAUUCUGCAAACGAGGAAUUCAGACCAGAGAUGCUCCAAGGAAAGAAAGUGAUUGUCACAGGGGCCAGCAAAGGGAUCGGAAGAGAGAUGGCUUAUCAUCUGGCGAAGAUGGGAGCCCAUGUGGUGGUGACAGCGAGGUCAAAAGAAACUCUACAGAAGGUGGUAUCCCACUGCCUGGAGCUUGGAGCAGCCUCAGCACACUACAUUGCUGGCACCAUGGAAGACAUGACCUUCGCAGAGCAAUUUGUUGCCCAAGCAGGAAAGCUCAUGGGAGGACUAGACAUGCUCAUUCUCAACCACAUCACCAACACUUCUUUGAAUCUUUUUCAUGAUGAUAUUCACCAUGUGCGCAAAAGCAUGGAAGUCAACUUCCUCAGUUACGUGGUCCUGACUGUAGCUGCCUUGCCCAUGCUGAAGCAGAGCAAUGGAAGCAUUGUUGUCGUCUCCUCUCUGGCUGGGAAAGUGGCUUAUCCAAUGGUUGCUGCCUAUUCUGCAAGCAAGUUUGCUUUGGAUGGGUUCUUCUCCUCCAUCAGAAAGGAAUAUUCAGUGUCCAGGGUCAAUGUAUCAAUCACUCUCUGUGUUCUUGGCCUCAUAGACACAGAAACAGCCAUGAAGGCAGUUUCUGGGAUAGUCCAUAUGCAAGCAGCUCCAAAGGAGGAAUGUGCCCUGGAGAUCAUCAAAGGGGGAGCUCUGCGCCAAGAAGAAGUGUAUUAUGACAGCUCACUCUGGACCACUCUUCUGAUCAGAAAUCCAUGCAGGAAGAUCCUGGAAUUUCUCUACUCAACGAGCUAUAAUAUGGACAGAUUCAUAAACAAGUAGGAACUCCCUGAGGGCUGGGCAUGCUGAGGGAUUUUGGGACUGUUCUGUCUCAUGUUUAUCUGAGCUCUUAUCUAUGAAGACAUCUUCCCAGAGUGUCCCCAGAGACAUGCAAGUCAUGGGUCACACCUGACAAAUGGAAGGAGUUCCUCUAACAUUUGCAAAAUGGAAAUGUAAUAAUAAUGAAUGUCAUGCACCGCUGCAGCCAGCAGUUGUAAAAUUGUUAGUAAACAUAGGUAUAAUUACCAGAUAGUUAUAUUAAAUUUAUAUCUUAUAUAUAAUAAUAUGUGAUGAUUAAUACAAUAUUAAUUAUAAUAAAGGUCACAUAAACUUUAUAAAUUCAUAACUGGUAGCUAUAACUUGAGCUUAUUCAGGAUGGUUUCUUUAAAACCAUAAACUGUACAAAUGAAA